GAGCUGGGCCCGCUGCCGACGCGGCUGGGAGCCCAGCGGGUCCCGCAGCGGUUCGCGCUGAAGUGGCAUCUCUCUCCCGCCCCGCUUCCCCCUGGGUCCUUAUCCUCCGAGACCUUUACCUCAUCCUCGACCUUUACCCUCAUCCAUUUCCCCCUCCUAAUCCUUGCUCCUGUGUCCCCCGUAACUGAAUAUCUCCACUCCUGGCGCCCCCCACGUUUCUUCCCUCCCGCCGCAAACCUCGCGACCUCCAGCAGCCCGCCCCCGCGGGCCCGAUCCUGCCUGGCGGCUCCCGCCGCAGCCUCCUCAGCCUUCCCGCUCUGCCGGGGUUCGCCCCACUACGCCCCCGGUCGUCAGCCCUCGGGCUUCCCUGCUCCCCCCUCCCGUCCCCUCGGAGCCCCCUCCCCCGCCUCGGCCAGCCAGCAUGCAGGUGUCUAUCGCGUGUACCGAGCAGAACCUUCGCAGCCGGAGCAGUGAGGACCGUCUGUGUGGACCCCGGCCGGGCCCCGGGGGCGGUAAUGGUGGGCCGGCCGGCGGGGGGCACGGGAAUCCUCCGGGGGGUGGAGGGUCUGGCCCCAAGGCCCGAGCUGCACUGGUUCCCCGACCCCCAGCGCCCGCUGGGGCCCUCCGAGAGAGCACCGGCCGAGGCACUGGCAUGAAAUACAGGUAUGGGGGUGGCCGGGCAGCCCACCCCUUCCGCUUUCCUUUCGGGACCCCUGAGACUGCUUGAGAUGGCCGCCAAGACCCCUUCAAACUUCACUAAGAACCUAGGGAAGUCUGGUCUUCGGGUAUCCUGUCUUGGCCUAGGUACCUGGGUCACAUUUGGUUCUCAGAUCUCAGAUGAGACAGCAGAGGAUGUGCUGACUGUAGCCUAUGAGCAUGGUGUAAACCUGUUUGACACCGCCGAAGUGUACGCAGCAGGAAAGGCUGAAAGAACCCUAGGGAACAUCCUCAAGAGCAAAGGUUGGAGGAGAUCAAGCUAUGUCAUCACUACCAAGAUUUUUUGGGGAGGACAGGCAGAAACCGAGCGAGGUUUAAGCCGAAAGCACAUCAUUGAGGGCUUGCGAGGAUCCCUGGAACGCCUCCAGCUGGGAUACGUGGACAUUGUCUUUGCCAAUCGCUCAGACCCCAACUGUCCUAUGGAGGAGAUUGUGCGAGCCAUGACCUAUGUCAUCAACCAGGGCCUGGCCCUAUACUGGGGGACAUCCCGAUGGGGGGCUGCAGAAAUCAUGGAGGCCUACUCCAUGGCCAGACAGUUCAAUCUGAUUCCUCCAGUGUGUGAACAAGCGGAGCACCAUCUGUUUCAGAGGGAGAAGGUGGAGAUGCAGCUGCCAGAGCUCUACCACAAGAUUGGAGUUGGAUCAGUCACUUGGUACCCUCUAGCCUGUGGUCUCAUUACUAGCAAGUAUGAUGGGCGAGUCCCAGAUACUUGCAGGGCCUCCAUCAAGGGCUACCAGUGGCUCAAGGACAAAGUGCAGAGUGAAGAUGGCAAGAAGCAACAAGCCAAAGUCAUGGACCUUCUUCCUGUCGCUCACCAGCUGGGCUGCACCGUGGCCCAGCUUGCUAUUGCGUGGUGUCUCCGCAGUGAGGGUGUCAGCUCUGUCUUGCUGGGGGUGUCGAGUGCGGAGCAGUUGAUAGAACACCUGGGCGCGCUACAGGUGCUGAGCCAGCUGACCCCGCAGACAGUGAUGGAAAUAGACGGGCUCCUGGGAAACAAGCCGCAUUCCAAGAAGUAGUCUGUCGCGGGCGCAGGGACCCAACCCGGUGUCGCUGCACCCGCCCGAGCCCCGCUCCUCGCAGCCGCCUCUCCCGCUCCGGAUCCCUCCACGCAGCGGCCGGAGCCAGACUAGCCCCGCCCACCAACGAGUCCCGGCUUCGAGUAGUGAUACGCAUGAACAAAGCCAUAUCCUUUUGCAGUGGGGUCGAGAGAGAAAGUAGCACGCCCGCCCCCUGCUGCGUCUUUCUAGGCCCUUCUUGCAAAUCCCGGGCAUGAGCUACUCGCCGUCGGCUCUCUGCCACUUCGUCUCGCUCCCUACUCUCCUCCCCUUAUUCCCGAGGCCCAGAAAAGAAAACAAAAACAAAAACCCAGCACAUACAAGAAACAUACAGUGUACCUCAAAAGGGGCCCUUGAAAUGUCAUCAAAGGGUAAUAACCUAGUGAGUGAGUUGUGAUGUCAUCUGGAACAUAGGAAAUGGGGCUCUUAGCGUAUUCGGUACGAAGGAAGCCAGGCUGGUCCUGGCAGGAAGUAAAUGAUAAUCUUUGGGAAACCAGGACCCUGCCUCCCAGCCCAGAGGUGGAGGAGGGCGGUCAGGGUGGGGUCUACAGUGGCACAGCACUGACAAAGGUAGAGGGAAAUGUAAUAGCACAUCUACGCUGCAGUCUGGUGAAAGUGGCCGGGGUGGUCCUUGGAAAACAGUUGGGCUGUUCUUGGCAGGAAUUAGUGACAGCCUUUCCGUCACGGGCAGGGACGCCUUGAUUUAAAAAAAAUAAAUAAAUAAAACGUCUGGGUAUAGACUUUUGAGCCUUGAGCAGGGCCUCCUACCUGGCAGUGGGGAACUGCAGUCUUCCUCCUGGCAAUAAACCUAAAGCAAUAAUGAUGGCCCCUUCUCUGUAAGACUUCCCAGGUAACUGUAAAUAAACCUCAGCUUGAUCCUCACAGUGUCUAAAGUUGCAGGGGCUUGGGAGGUUAGGGUCACAGUCUCACUUGUCUGGCCCUCUCGCCCCCUAACAUUAGAAAUCUGCUAGCAUUAGCUUUCUCUCCAUUGCUCAUUCACCUUGGUGACCCAGGCAUCGGGCUCCUAGUCACUGUUCUCAUCAAGGACCAAGACACCAGAUACCCCAGGCCCCAGUUUUCUUCCUUCAGCUACCACAUUCCUUAGAACCCAGAAAUCUGGCUUCAUAAUUUUGUUCCUCCUCUUUCUAUGAAAGACUUAGCUAUCUGCCUUUAUUUGUUUGUAUUUAAAGUAAUAUUAGCCAUA